GCCUCCCAAAGUGCUGGGAUUACAGGCGUGAGCCACCGUGCCCAGCCGAGAAGAAAAUUUAUUGAAGGUCAAUUGUUGACAAGUCAUUAGGCACUUACUCCCCUCAAAACAACCCCAUGAGAUAAUUUCUCCCUUAUAUAAAUGAGGAAGUUGAGCCUUAGAAAUGUUAAGUAACUUAUCCAAAGCUACAUAGCUAGAAAGUGAAGCAGGUAGGUUGUCAGUUUAGACUGCAUUCUACCAAGCUUUAAUACAGGGAUGAGUAGUAGCCACUUUGGCAUGGCCACAGGGGAAUCCAGAAAAAAGAAUGAAUCUGGAAACCUUAUUUUUGAAUUGCCUUUUUCCCACUAGAAAACCUGAGAUACCCAGCACCUGCCUAGUGUAUGGUCUGUUAAGCCUAUGAUCUAGGUACUGUAUGGCUGGGUCCCAAGCCCUGCCUCCUUAAACCUAGUUCCUAGAAUGUAUGAUUAGAGGGGGAGUCCUUUCCUGCCACUCUGUAUAACUAGUUGUGACUAGUUUCAUGGCCUGUAUUACUGUUGUUUUUUGUUACUUGGUGAUUGCAUAUAGGAUGUAAAUAUUUUCUUGGAAGUUGAAAAAAUAAAUUAGGUGAGACUAUAUCUACUUGAACUCUUCCUACAGAUCUAUAGCUCUCAUCACCUUCUAUCCGGAUCAACCUUGUGGUUUGAGUUUUAACAACCUGGCCUGGAAACAGAAUGUUUUGUGUUUCAAGGAGAGAUUAUUGGAGAAAAUGUUCAGAAGAAUCCAGGUUCUGGGGCUGCUGGUAUGGACGCUUAUUGCUGGAACUGAGUACUUCCGGGUCCCCGCAUUUGGCUGGGUCAUGUUUGUAGCUGUAUUUUACUGGGUCCUCACCGUCUUCUUCCUCAUUAUCUACAUAACAAUGACCUACACCAGGAUUCCCCAGGUGCCCUGGACAACAGUGGGCCUGUGCUUUAACGGCAGUGCCUUCGUCUUGUACCUCUCUGCCGCUGUUGUAGAUGCAUCUUCCGUCUCCCCUGAGAGGGACAGUCACAACUUCAACAGCUGGGCGGCCUCAUCGUUCUUUGCCUUCCUGGUCACCAUCUGCUACGCUGGAAAUACAUAUUUCAGUUUUAUAGCAUGGAGAUCCAGGACCAUACAGUGAUUUACCAUUUUGAUAAUUAAAAGGAAAAAAAAAGGAAGACUCUCACUGUAAAAACAGCUGUAGGUAUAAUGUAUAUUCCCAGAGAAUUGUAUUUAACUAAUUAAUGUUUUUUAUAUUCUUAAAUUUGCUCACAAAUUGUGGUUUGUUACAAUUAAACUGGAUACUUAUUUGCAAAGUGUUGUAGCUUAUAAUGAACUCUUAAGUAUCUUAUUAAUGUAUUAAUGUCUUCAUAGAUCAUAUUUUCUUAGACAAUGUUUAAAUAGAUAAAUUGCUAAUAUUGAGAAUGUGUCAAGUUUGUAAACCUAACUUUUAAGAUGCCAGAUUCUUUUUUGAUUAAAUGUUGCAAAAUCCCAA